GACAGGAGCCAGGACCCGUGUAGGAGAUGGUUCUCGCCAUGCUGGGGGCUCUGCACCCCCGGGCUGGGCUCAGCCUCUUCCUCCACCUCAUCCUGGCAGUGGCACUGCUUCGCUCCCAGCCUCUGAGGUCUCAGCGGUCUGUUCCUGAGGCAUUUUCCGCCCCCCUGGAACUCUCGCAGCCACUUUCCGGCCUGGUGGAUGACUAUGGCAUCCUCCCCAAGCACCCAAGGCCGCGAGGGCCUCGACCCCUCCUGUCUAGGGCCCAGCAGCGCAAGCGGGACGGGCCCGACCUUGCCGAGUAUUACUAUGAUGCACACCUAUGACCCAAGGCCCUCAUAAAGAUACCAUGUGUGACAAA